UUGCUGUGUCACCCAGGCUGGAGUGCAGUGGCGCGAUCUCAGCUCACUGCAAGUUCCGCCUCCCGGGUUCACACCAUUCUCCUGCUUCAGCCUCCCGAGUAGCUGGGACUGCAGGUGCCCGCCACCUCGCCGGCUCAUUUUUUUAUUUUUAGUAGAGACUGGGUUUCACCGUAUUAGCCGGGAUGGUCUCGAUUUCCUGACCUCGUGAUCCGCCCGCCUCGGCCUCCCAAAGUGCUUGGGAUUACAGGCGUGAGCCACUGCACCCGGCCAGACUGCAGUAUUUUUAUUCCCUCAACUAACUUAAGGAUUGUAUCUUAAGAGUGGGAUAGAAAUGGUGUUUUAGGGAACCUCUGCAUAAGUAUACUUUGUUUGCCAAGUAAUACAAAGUGAGUAUUUGUGUGGAAAUGAUGGAAUAAAGGAGGGAGGGUAGGCAGUGAGGCAAAUGGUUACAUUCUUAUAAGGCUCUGGUUAGCCUCAGUAAAUCUAUACUUUACAUAUGAAAAGAGGGAGUAGAGGAAAAAGUCAGUUACGCAUUCAUCUCAGGGUAGGCCAAGGGAUGAUUUCUGGUUUUUAUCCUUGUCUUCUACCUGUGAAGAUAAGCUGGUAAUUGACAUUGUUAAGGUGAGCUUCAACAGAACUCAGUUUCCGGGCUAGUUUAUAGGGAAGAUAUGUAUCCUGAAAGAUUAAGACGAGGGAAGCCAUCUUGGGAGAUACGUGACCCUCUAUUGUUGUGGGAAUGUGGCUUAUGGAUGAGGCUACAUAUGUCUUGGUUGUGAAAUUACAGCUAUCUGUUUGGGAACAAAAGGAAAGUAGUAUUGCCUUACUUAGUUCCUAAGCUUAACUUCCCCUUUGGCAUCGUGCGUUUAGAGUCCCGAGAUUCUAUUUUCUUUUCACAUCAUUACUGUCUUCCAGGAUGUACUUGUUAAAGAGUUACUCUGCCAUGCUAGAUUCAGACCCACCUCCCCGCCAAUCUUGGACAAGUUGAACAUGGUCACCCAGUUCUUUGAUAGAUUUCACCUGCUCAUUCAGCAAUGUCUCAGGCUGUGCAGACAAACGGAACUCAACCAUUAAGCAAAACAUGGGAACUCAGUUUAUAUGAGUUACAACGAACACCUCAGGAGGCAAUAACAGAUGGCUUAGAAAUUGUGGUUUCACCUCGAAGUCUACACAGUGAAUUAAUGUGCCCAAUUUGUUUGGAUAUGUUGAAGAACACCAUGACUACAAAGGAGUGUUUACAUCGUUUUUGUGCAGACUGCAUCAUCACAGCCCUUAGAAGUGGCAACAAAGAAUGUCCUACCUGUCGGAAAAAACUAGUUUCCAAAAGAUCACUAAGGCCAGACCCAAACUUUGAUGCACUCAUCAGCAAAAUUUAUCCAAGUCGUGAUGAGUAUGAAGCUCAUCAAGAGAGAGUAUUAGCCAGGAUCAACAAGCACAAUAAUCAGCAAGCACUCAGUCACAGCAUUGAGGAAGGACUGAAGAUACAGGCCAUGAACAGACUGCAGCGAGGCAAGAAACAACAGAUUGAAAAUGGUAGUGGAGCAGAAGAUAAUGGUGACAGUUCACACUGCAGUAAUGCAUCCACACAUAGCAAUCAGGAAGCAGGCCCUAGUAACAAACGGACCAAAACAUCUGAUGAUUCUGGGCUAGAGCUUGAUAAUAACAAUGCAGCAAUGGCAAUUGAUCCAGUAAUGGAUGGUGCUAGUGAAAUUGAAUUAGUAUUCAGGCCUCAUCCCACACUUAUGGAAAAAGAUGACAGUGCACAGACGAGAUACAUAAAGACUUCUGGUAACGCCACUGUUGAUCACUUAUCCAAGUAUCUGGCUGUGAGGUUAGCUUUAGAAGAACUUCGAAGCAAAGGUGAAUCAAACCAGAUGAACCUUGAUACAGCCAGUGAGAAGCAGUAUACCAUUUAUAUAGCAACAGCCAGUGGCCAGUUCACUGUAUUAAAUGGCUCUUUUUCUUUGGAAUUGGUCAGUGAGAAAUACUGGAAAGUGAACAAACCCAUGGAACUUUAUUACGCACCUACAAAGGAGCACAAAUGAGCCUUUAAAAACCAAUUCUGAGACUGAACUUUUUUAUAGCCUAUUUCUUUAAUAUUAAAGAUGUACUGGCAUUACUUUUAUGGACAGAUCUUGGAUAUGUUGUUCAAUUUUCUUUCUGAGCCAGACUAGUUUACGCUAUUCAAAUCUUUUCCCCUUUAUUUAAGAUUUCCUUUUUGGAAGGGACUGCAAUUAUUCAGUAUUUUUUUCUUUCCUUUAAAAAAAUAUAUCUGAAGUUUCUUGUGUUUUUUUUUUUCCCCACAAAGUGUGUUUCCACUUGGAGCACCAUUUUGACCCAGGAAUUUUUCAUAGUUUCUGUAUUCUUAUAAGAUUCAGUUGGCUGUCCUUUUCCUGCUCCCCUCAAAAGAUUUUUAGUCAUACAGAAUGUUAAAUAUUAUGUAUUCUGACUUUUUUUUUCCCCCGGAGUCUUGUAUAUUUAUAGUUUUCUAUAUAAACUGUAGUAUCUUCAUGAAGACCCAAGGCUCAAAUUUACUGUCCUUAAAAACAAUUCUCAUAGGAUUAUUCUUUUCAUGGUAUUUUCUUCCAUAAUAUCUCAUUUUAAAAAGAAGUUCUUUAUGAACUUAGUGUCCAUUGUCAUGCAAUGUUUUUUUUUUUCCAUUCUUUUUCCCUGUAAUUUUGGAAUUUCUGGUCCUGGGAAGAAUCAAACAAAAUCUUAAGUUCUAUGAGAACUUGGUUCAUUGACAUAUUCUGCUGAAGAAAGAAAAAUUAAAUUGGUAGUAAAAUAUAGUCUUCAAGUAUACGUUUGAGAGUGCUUUUUUUUGUAUUAGUUCUGCUGUCACUUCAUUUCCUGUAUUAUAUGUGAUGUUUUUCCCCAUUAAAAUACCAGAGAUAAUGGAGAUAUUUUGCACUUUAGCCUUGAUGAAAAGUACAAGAUAUGUUCAAAGCUUCCCUAAUUUUUUUCUUAUUUGUAGCCACAUAAGUUUCAAGAAUAACAUGGCACACAGAACAAUGGAAAAAAGUUUGUUUCCAUUGGAAAAUUAUAUCAUUUUGGGUUGCCACAUCAGUUUAUAAAUUUGGCGCUCUUUUAAUUACACUCUGUAGAAGGUUAAUAGAGCUUGAGCCCUGCUUUAAUAUGUAGUGAAAGAUAAUUCUGUAGAAAAACGUCAGCCAGUAGGGUAAAGUCAUUCUACUGUUCUUAAUUUUUAUAUUGAGGAACAAUAUUGGGUGUUUGGGAGCCAGAAAGCUUUGUUGACAGAUCAGAAAUAAGAUUGACUUGGGUGUUAUAUUUCAUCUCUCUCCAGACUCUAGGUAUAUUUCCAACUUUAUAUAUCACAGUAUUUAAAAAGACAUGUUUGCAUUGAGAAAUUAACCCUAAAGGGUUUUCAAUAGGGUGUAGACCUCCAGUACCUUUGUAACUAAAGUCUGUCUAGUCAUUGUAAAUAUUUAUCUGUCAGUUUUGACAGAUUGGGGCCAGCUUGAUGUUUUAAAUCUUCAGCCCGGUAUGAAAACUUAAAGGUAUAUAUUCAAUUUUUUACCAUUUUAUGGAAAAUAUUUAAAAUCUGUUUUUACAGGGUUUUUUUUUUUUUUUUUUUUUUGUAAUCUGUGCCAUGAAAUUUGAAAACCACCAAAAAUCAAGGGAACUUUUAUAUAUUCAAUUCCUUUUCUGGUGUAAUGUUAAAGUUGUAUAGAUUAUUAAUGCAUGCCCACUGAAUAUAACCCUGGUUUUGUGAUAAAACUGCUUAGAUUUUGUUGAUGACAUUAGAUUAGUAGUUGCAUUAAAUAACUAAAUUCCCAUUGUGAUUAAUUGAAAUUUUGUCUUUAAGCAGAGAGUUAUUUGUGACUAUAAGCUUUGUGCUUAGAGAAUGUAUGUGUUUUUAUCUGUCAGUAUGGGAGGAUAUAAACUGCAUCAUUAGUGAAAUUAUUGGUUGUGUAAUCCUUUGUGAAAUAUAAUUCUAGGUAUUUGAUAGGGUAUUGAGUGUAUUUUGUGUGUGUGUGGAUGUGUGUUUUGGGGUACGGGGAGAGGCGAUGCUAUUGGCCAUCACUACCAACCAGGGUUUCAAAAAGUAUUACCUAAGUAAUUUCUUUUAUCACUAUCUCAACUGAGGAAGAAAAGGCUCACCACAAGUGGUGUGAAGGCUUUGGGUACUUAGUUCUAAAUUUUUUUAUGGUAACAUAUACAUAGCCACAUUUACAGUUUUAACCAUUUUAAGGCAUGUAAUUCAGUGGGGUUAGGUACAUUCACAAUGUUGUGUAAUGAUCACCGCUGUCUACUUGUAAAACUUUUUCAUCACCCCAAACAGAAACUCUGUGUGCAAUUAAAGUAAUGCAUUUCUCUUCUUCUUAA